CUCUCCUCUCUGUUCUUCGACCUCUGGGAGUGAAUCCUACCCUUCCCGUGUACUGAAGAUCCAGCGUUUAGUUCUCCUUUGAUUUCCUCUCCCUCUGGCCACCCCUGCCCCCAAUCGUAAAAGGGGUCAGUCUGCUCAGGCCUGCUUUGAUGGGACCCCGAAGGCCAGGAAGGAACUGGUCCUGGGUUUUCUAAGAGCUGGGGGCGGAUGGAAUUCUCCUGCCUGCGGGUCUUUAAAGACUGAGACCCGGGAAAAGGAGAAGAUGAAGGAAGCCAAGGAUGCCCGCUAUACCAAUGGGCACCUCUUCACCACCAUUUCAGUUUCAGGCAUGACCAUGUGCUAUGCCUGUAACAAGAGCAUCACAGCCAAGGAAGCCCUCAUCUGCCCAACCUGCAAUGUGACUAUCCACAACCGCUGUAAAGACACCCUCGCCAACUGUACCAAGGUCAAGCAGAAGCAACAGAAAGCGGCCCUGCUGAAGAACAACACCGCCUUGCAGUCCGUUUCUCUUCGAAGUAAGACAACCAUCCGGGAGCGGCCAAGCUCGGCCAUCUACCCCUCCGACAGCUUCCGGCAGUCCCUCCUGGGCUCCCGCCGUGGCCGCUCCUCCUUGUCUUUAGCCAAGAGUGUUUCUACCACCAACAUUGCUGGACAUUUCAAUGAUGAGUCUCCCCUGGGGCUGCGCCGGAUCCUCUCACAGUCCACAGACUCCCUCAACAUGCGGAACCGAACCCUAUCCGUGGAAUCCCUCAUUGACGAAGCAGAGGUAAUCUACAGUGAGCUGAUGAGUGACUUUGAGAUGGAUGAGAAGGACUUUGCAGCUGACUCUUGGAGUCUUGCUGUGGACAGCAGCUUCCUGCAGCAGCAUAAAAAGGAGGUGAUGAAGCAGCAAGAUGUCAUCUAUGAGCUAAUCCAGACAGAGCUGCACCAUGUGAGGACACUGAAGAUCAUGACCCGCCUCUUCCGCACGGGGAUGCUGGAAGAGCUACACUUGGAGCCAGGAGUGGUCCAGGGCCUGUUCCCCUGCGUGGACGAGCUCAGUGACAUCCAUACACGCUUCCUCAGCCAGCUAUUAGAACGCCGACGCCAGGCCCUGUGCCCUGGCAGCACCCGGAACUUUGUCAUCCAUCGCUUGGGUGAUCUGCUCAUCAGCCAGUUCUCAGGUCCUAGUGCGGAGCAGAUGUGUAAGACCUACUCGGAGUUCUGCAGCCGCCACAGCAAGGCCUUAAAGCUCUAUAAGGAGCUGUACGCCCGAGACAAACGCUUCCAGCAAUUCAUCCGGAAAGUGACCCGCCCCGCCGUGCUCAAGCGGCACGGGGUACAGGAGUGCAUCCUGCUGGUGACUCAGCGCAUCACCAAGUACCCGUUACUCAUCAGCCGCAUCCUGCAGCAUUCCCACGGGAUCGAGGAGGAGCGCCAGGACCUGACCACAGCACUGGGGCUAGUGAAGGAGCUGCUGUCCAAUGUGGACGAGGGUAUUUAUCAGCUGGAGAAAGGGGCCCGUCUGCAGGAGAUCUACAACCGCAUGGACCCUCGGGCCCAAACCCCAGUGCCUGGCAAGGGCCCCUUUGGCCGAGAGGAACUUCUGAGGCGCAAACUCAUCCACGAUGGCUGCCUGCUCUGGAAGACAGCGACGGGGCGCUUCAAAGAUGUGCUAGUGCUGCUGAUGACAGAUGUACUGGUGUUUCUCCAGGAAAAGGACCAGAAGUACAUCUUUCCUACCCUGGACAAGCCUUCAGUGGUAUCGCUGCAGAAUCUAAUCGUACGAGACAUUGCCAACCAGGAGAAAGGGAUGUUUCUGAUCAGCGCAGCCCCACCUGAGAUGUACGAGGUGCACACAGCAUCCCGGGAUGACCGGAGCACCUGGAUCCGGGUCAUUCAGCAGAGCGUGCGCACAUGCCCAUCCAGGGAGGACUUCCCCCUGAUUGAGACAGAGGAUGAGGCUUACCUGCGGCGAAUUAAGAUGGAGUUGCAGCAGAAGGACCGGGCACUGGUGGAGCUGCUGCGAGAGAAGGUCGGGCUGUUUGCUGAGAUGACCCAUUUCCAGGCCGAAGAGGAUGGUGGCAGUGGGAUGGCCCUGCCCACCCUGCCCAGGGGCCUUUUCCGCUCUGAGUCCCUUGAGUCCCCUCGUGGCGAGCGGCUGCUGCAGGAUGCCAUCCGUGAGGUGGAGGGUCUGAAAGACCUGCUGGUGGGGCCAGGAGUGGAACUGCUCUUGACACCCCGAGAGCCAGCCCUGCCCUUGGAACCAGACAGCGGUGGUAACACGAGUCCUGGGGUCACUGCCAAUGGUGAGGCCAGAACCUUCAAUGGCUCCAUUGAACUCUGCAGAGCUGACUCAGACUCUAGCCAGAGGGAUCGAAAUGGAAAUCAGCUGAGAUCACCGCAAGAGGAGGCGUUACAGCGAUUGGUCAAUCUCUAUGGACUUCUACAUGGCCUACAGGCAGCUGUGGCCCAGCAGGACACUCUGAUGGAAGCCCGGUUCCCUGAGGGCCCUGAGCGGCGGGAGAAGCUGUGCCGAGCCAACUCUCGGGAUGGGGAGGCUGGCAGGGCUGGGGCUGCCCCUGUGGCCCCUGAAAAGCAGGCCACGGAACUGGCAUUACUGCAGCGGCAACAUGCGCUGCUGCAGGAGGAGCUACGGCGCUGCCGGCGGCUAGGUGAAGAACGGGCAACCGAAGCUGGCAGCCUGGAGGCCCGGCUCCGGGAGAGUGAGCAGGCCCGGGCACUGCUGGAGCGUGAGGCCGAAGAGGCUCGAAGGCAGCUGGCCGCCCUGGGCCAGACCGAGCCACUCCCAGCUGAGGCCCCCUGGGCCCGCAGACCUGUGGAUCCUCGGCGGCGCAGCCUCCCCGCAGGCGAUGCCCUGUACUUGAGUUUCAACCCCCCACAGCCCAGCCGAGGCACUGACCGCCUGGAUCUACCUGUCACUACUCGCUCUGUCCAUCGAAACUUUGAGGACCGAGAGAGGCAGGAACUGGGGAGCCCCGAAGAGCGGCUGCAAGACAGCAGUGACCCUGACACUGGCAGCGAGGAGGAAGGUAGCAGCCGUCUGUCUCCGCCCCACAGUCCACGAGGUGAGACCCUGGCGGAGACAUGGACCAGAGACUUUACCAGAAUGCAGGACAUCCCGGAGGAGACGGAGAGCCGCGACGGGGAGGCUGUAGCCUCCGAGAGCUAAGGGGGCCCCUCCCCCCUGCCCCGUGCCCCACUGAAGAACAUUACUGAGGGGGCUAACCUUGGGGACUCCAAUUUGCCAAUGAUGAGGGAACAUUUGAAAGAACUGCAAAUUGUCCUUGCCAGCUCUUGGGAUCCUUGGAUACCUGGGGCCAUUUAAGAAGCUAGGGGAAUUAGGCCACAACACCCCCUGGGACAUCCGAAAGCUACACCACAGAUGCCAGUGGUUCAUGCCUUCUUCCCGCAACUUUAGGAAAAUUUAUUUAUUUAUUGUUUAUUAGUUAUGGGGGGAGAGGGGAGAUUUAAAGGACCAGGGACAUGGGAACCAAGCCAUAGGGAUCAGAGGGCCUUGUCCUUGAACACUACUGGGGUAUAUUCAGGCUCAUCCACGCAGCUGCUGGGUUCUUGCCCUAACGGCCCUCCCCUGCAACAUCCGUCUUGGAGGAGAGGCUGCAGCCACAGCACCCUACUGCCCUUUAAAUAAAGGAGGGCUGUGGGCAGGGCCAUGUCCCUUUCUCCUCUCCCCUCAACCUCUUACUGCUGUUCUCCCUUUCUCCGUCCUUCAUGGAAGCCCUGGGAGAUAACCUGGCUUCCUGGAGUUGAUGGAAUAAAGGUUGGGGUGGCCAUAAUGGUUUGUUGGGGGUGAGGGAAAAAACCCACAGGGACCAGAAUGUUUUGUUGUUCUUUUGUUUUCUUUUUUGUACCAAAGUCAACUGCACGUGUUUUAUAUUUUUAAGAGAUCGUAGGCAAUUAGAGAUCGAAGCCUCCUAUCUCCACAUCUCUGAAGAAGUUGAGGGGUGGGGGAGAGAAUGACUUCUGCCUUCAUCUGCAGUAACGGGGGGACCUAUACUGACCUCUUCCCCAGCCAUUUAGAAACAAGUUCUAGGGUGGGUUGGAAAAUCUCCAAGAGCCCUGACCUCAUCUUCCACCUCAGCAACCAUGACCUGAAACCUCAGCGUGAAUUUGGGGGAUUUUUCAGUGGAACCCUUGCCCCCAAAUGUCGACCAGCCCCCAAAUGUCGAAGAAUUUUCUUCUUGCCAAUUUUGUUGUUUAAAAAAAAAAUUCAGGGAAAAUUAAAAACCUGGAACUCCA